AUAGAGCAUAGCUGGCGAUCGUGUACUUACACUCUAAGGUCACCUGGUUGCACUGUGGCCUCAUCUGUGGCUCUGAAAAUGAAGAUUUGGAAGGAGAUCAUCACAGCUAAUGUUAACAAGCCCCUCCUGUGUGCCAAAUCAUUCACCCCUCACCACAACCGAAUGAGCUAAGGAUUCUCAUUAUAUAUAGUUUAUGGAGAGGGAAGUGCAGACAUAAAGAGGUGAAUUAUCUUACCCAGAUCACACAGCUGAUAAGUGGUGGAGGCAGAAUAGAAUCUAAACAGUGUGGCUCCGGAGCCCACAUGCAUUGAUUCGACAAGUGUUUAUUGAGCACCUGCCACGGACAAGGCCUUGUGUGAUUAAAUAGGGUUAUAAUUAGUAAUAUAAAAAUGAGAAAUCACUAAUGCUUUUUAGACUUAACAUUUUCUUUUUUUGUAGGUUUCAGGCACAGAACUGUAUAUCCAAUAAUAGUGAAAUGGAUCCCACUAAUUAUGACAGAAAUGAUGAUACAUUUAAAUGACUUGGAUGUUUUAUAGGUAUGAUCUCGUGAAACCUUGAGAGAAACUGAAUGACGAAUGAAACUAUUGUUCCUGUUUCACACAGAAGAAAACUGAGGUUAAAAGGGGUUGGCACUCAUCAUGAGCCCCUGUUCUCAUUCUGCAAAUGGUGAAGCUCUCUAUUGUCCUGACCCCACAGUUCCUGUCCCAUGACCAGGGCCAGCUCACCAAGGAGCUGCAGCAGCAUGUAAAGUCAGUGACAUGCCCAUGCGAGUACCUGAGGAAGGUUGAUGGACGGAUGGCUACAUGGAUGUGAUGGAGAUGGUUUACUAUCGGGACCUUCCGCACCCUGCUGAUGUUUUGUUGCUUAGGAUAUGAAUGGCUGAGCGGAGGCUGUAAAACCUGGCACUCUGCUUGGGUUAUCAAUACUCUGGCUGACCAUCAUCAUCGUGGGACUGACUUUGGUGGAAGUCCUUGGUUACAUGUCAUUAUUGCGUUUCCGACAAGUUAUAAAGUUGUCAUUACCCUCUGGAUAGUUUACCUUUGGGUGUCUCUCCUGAAGACUAUCUUCUGGUCUCGAAAUGGACAUGAUGGAUCCACGGAUGUACAGCAGAGAGCCUGGAGGUCCAACCGCCGUAGACAGGAAGGGCUGAGGUCCAUUUGUAUGCACACAAAGAAAAGAGUUUCUUCCUUUCGAGGAAAUAAAAUUGGCCUGAAAGACGUCAUUACUCUACGGAGACAUGUGGAAACAAAAGUUAGAGCUAAAAUCCGUAAGAGGAAGGUGACAACGAAAAUCAACCAUCAUGACAAAAUCAAUGGAAAGAGGAAGACCGCCAGAAAACAGAAAAUGUUUCAACGUGCGCAAGAGUUGCGGCGGCGGGCAGAGGACUACCACAAAUGCAAAAUCCCCCCUUCUGCAAGAAAGGCUCUUUGCAACUGGGUCAGAAUGGCGGCAGCGGAGCAUCGUCAUUCUUCAGGAUUGCCCUACUGGCCCUACCUCACAGCUGAAACUUUAAAAAACAGGAUGGGCCACCAGCCACCUCCUCCAACUCAACAACAUUCUAUAACUGAUAACUCCCUGAGCCUCAAGACACCUCCCGAGUGUGUGCUCACUCCCCUUCCACCCUCAGCGGAUGAUAAUCUCAAGACACCUCCCGAGUGUGUGCUCACUCCCCUUCCACCCUCAGCGGAUGAUAAUCUCAAGACACCUCCUGAGUGUCUGCUCACUCCCCUUCCACCCUCAGCGGAUGAUAAUCUCAAGACACCUCCCGAGUGUCUGCUCACUCCCCUUCCACCCUCAGCGGAUGAUAAUCUCAAGACACCUCCCGAGUGUCUGCUCACUCCCCUUCCACCCUCAGCUCCACCCUCAGCUCCACCCUCAGCGGAUGAUAAUCUCAAGACACGUGCCGAGUGUCUGCUCCAUCCCCUUCCACCCUCAGCGGAUGAUAAUCUCAAGACACCUUCCGAGCGUCAGCUCACUCCCCUUCCACCCUCAGCUCCACCCUCAGCAGAUGAUAAUAUCAAGACACCUGCCGAGCGUCUGCGGGGGCCGCUUCCACCCUCAGCGGAUGAUAAUCUCAAGACACCUUCCGAGCGUCAGCUCACUCCCCUUCCACCCUCAGCUCCACCCUCAGCAGAUGAUAAUAUCAAGACACCUGCCUUCCACCCUCAGCGGAUGAUAAUCUCAAGACACCUUCCGAGCGUCAGCUCACUCCCCUUCCACCCUCAGCUCCACUCUCAGCAGAUGAUAAUAUCAAGAUACCUGCUGAGCGUCUGCGGAUUCCGCUUCCACCAUCAGCCGAUGAUAAUCUCAAGACACCUUCCGAGCGUCAGCUCACUCCCCUUCCACCCUCAGCUCCACCCUCAGCAGAUGAUAAUAUCAAGACACCUGCCGAGCGUCUGCGGGGGCCGCUUCCACCCUCAGCGGAUGAUAAUCUCAAGACACCUUCCGAGCGUCAGCUCACUCCCCUUCCACCCUCAGCUCCACCCUCAGCAGAUGAUAAUAUCAAGACACCUGCCGAGCGUCUGCGGGGGCCGCUUCCACCCUCAGCGGAUGAUAAUCUCAAGACACCUUCCGAGCGUCAGCUCACUCCCCUUCCACCCUCAGCUCCACCCUCAGCAGAUGAUAAUAUCAAGACACCUGCCGAGCGUCUGCGGGGGCCGCUUCCACCCUCAGCGGAUGAUAAUCUCAAGACACCUUCCGAGCGUCAGCUCACUCCCCUUCCACCCUCAGCUCCACCCUCAGCAGAUGAUAAUAUCAAGACACCUGCCGAGCGUCUGCGGGGAGCGUCUGCGGGGGCCGCUUCCACCCUCAGCGGAUGAUAAUCUCAAGACACCUUCCGAGCGUCAGCUCACUCCCCUUCCACCCUCAGCUCCACCCUCAGCAGAUGAUAAUAUCAAGACACCUGCCGAGCGUCUGCGGGGGCCGCUUCCACCCUCAGCGGAUGAUAAUCUCAAGACACCUUCCGAGCGUCAGCUCACUCCCCUUCCACCCUCAGCUCCACCCUCAGCAGAUGAUAAUAUCAAGACACCUGCCGAGCGUCUGCGGGGGCCGCUUCCACCCUCAGCGGAUGAUAAUCUCAAGACACCUUCUGAGCGUCAGCUCACUCCCCUUCCACCCUCAGCUCCACCCUCAGCAGAUGAUAAUAUCAAGACACCUGCCGAGCGUCUGCGGGGGCCGCUUCCACCCUCAGCCGAUGAUAAUCUCAAGACACCUCCCUUAGCUACUCAGGAGGCUGAGGCAGAAAAACCACGCAAACCCAAGAGGCAGAGGGCGGCUGAGAUGGAACCACCUCCCGAACCCAAGAGGCGGAGGGUCGGUGACGUGGAACCGUCACGCAAACCCAAGAGGCGGAGGGCCGCUGACGUGGAACCAUCAUCACCCGAACCCAAGAGGCGGAGGGUCGGUGAUGUGGAACCGUCACGCAAACCCAAGAGGCGGAGGGCCGCUGACGUGGAACCAUCAUCACCCGAACCCAAGAGGCGGAGGGUCGGUGACGUGGAACCGUCACGCAAACCCAAGAGGCGGAGGGCCGCUGACGUGGAACCAUCAUUACCCGAACCCAAGAGGCGGAGGUUGAGCUGAGAAGAGGCCAGUGCACUCAAGCCUGAGCAAUAAGAAUAAAACCGAGUAGAACAAAAUAAAAAAUUCAAAAAACAAAACAAAACCCACACUCCAAAAACUAACAAAGAAUAAAUAAAUAAUAUAAAAAUAAAAUAAAUACUGCAGUCCUUAUGUUA